AGAAGGAUAGAUCCUAUUAAAACUCAGUCGCAUUGGUUUAUAGAUAGACGUAAUCAAUGGAUGGCAUUGCAAGGAGCAUCCAGUUUUAUGGAGGGUGGAAGCCUCACUUCCUUGGCUAUAAUAAAGAGUUCUGAUGCAUCUUCAUACAACAAGAGGAAGAGUCUGCACGCAGAAGCACCACCUUCUAGGGAUAAAUAAAGGGUCAAGCUAAGGAAGGGCAGAACAAACUUCAGACACUCACUUCUUUGCCUCAACUUCAGCCUGCUCUCACAACCUCACUAUGUCUUGCCCCAACUACUGCUCGGGAAACUCCAACUCAGGAUCUCUCAGAACCUCCCGCCAUAUUCCUCUCACCUCCAUCGACCUCUGCCCUACCAGCGUGAGCUGUGGAGAUGUCCUCUACUUACCCACUAGCUCUCAAGACCAUACCUGGGUCACAGACAACUGCCAAGAGACCUGCGGUGAACCAACCAGCUGCCAGCCGGUCCACUGUGAGACCGGCAAUCUUGAAACCUCUUGCGGUUCUUCCACUGCUUACUACGUGCCCAGGCCUUGCCAAGGAAGCAGUUUUCUUCCUGCUUCUUUCUUCUCCAGUUCCUGCCUUCCAGUAUCCUGUAGACCACAGAGGUAUGUGUCCAGCGGCUGUCGUCCACUGAGGCCGCUGCUCAAUAGUUACCAGCCCAUAGGAGACUGUGUGCCCAAUGCCUAUCGCCCCCAAUUCUGCUUGUCCAAGAGUUGCCAGCCCCAAAACCUCCUCACUUCUGGAUGCCAACCCUCGAGUUGCUUGGCCUAUCGUCCUCAAAGUCUUCACGUUGUGUCCAGCAGCCUCAGACCUCUGGGGCCUCUGUUCAGUGGUUGCCAACCUCUGACCCAUGUGUUCAGCACGUGUCGUCCAUCUUGCUCUGGACUGUGAAACCAGCAGCUUCUUUGUUCCAGUGAAUAAUCACUCUGAGCAUCCACAACAAAAAUUCAAACUCCAUGGACUUUUGCUUCUUUGCUAGUAGCAACUGAUGUUUCUUAGUUUUACUGUGCCUGAUCUAAUGCAAGCUGCUUCUCUCGCAUGUUUUAUCUUGUUUUCAUCUUUCCUUGACAUCAAAAAAAUUAGUUUACAAUGCUAUUCAAUGUUGCUCUGGUCUGGGAAGAAUGUAUUUGUUUUGCACUAUAAUAAAUGCGAUUAAGUCCAAAUUAAGAA